UUGUUUUUCUUUUAAAUAGUAAUGGGGUUUAUCAGCUCUUGGAAUAACGGUCUGUAGGACUUAAUCAGGGCGCUGUCUCUGAGACCGGUCUUGGUUCUUCCUUUUUGACAUACUGUCUUCGUCUCCAGGCUGCUUGACCUUCUGUUGGUUCUUGGAGCAGAAAAGUCAGGAGUCUCUGUCCCGUCACUGGCAGUGUUGCCGAGGGGGAAGCGGGGAGGAGUGGGGCUCCCAGGUGAGAGGGGGCCCAGAGCCUCAUCCGCCCCGUUCAUUCUAGAACUCAGCACGUUUCUUUUUUUUUCUUUUUUGAGACAGAGUCUUGCUCUGUCGCCCAGGCUGGAGUGCAGCGGCACGAACUUGGCUCACUGCAAGCUCCACCUCCCGGGUUGACGCCAUUCUCCUGCCUCAGCCUCCCGAGUAGCUGGGACUACAGGCACCUGCCACCACGCCUGGCUAAUUUUUUGUAUUUUUAGUAGAGACGGGGUUUCACCGUGUUAGCCAGGAUGGUCUCGAUCUCCUGACCUCGUGAUCCGCCUGCCUCGGCCUCCCAAAGUGCUGGGAUUACAGGCGUGAGACACCGCGCCCGGCCCUCAGCAAGUUUCUACCAAGACAGGCAGCCCUAACCUGGCAGGUGGGGUUGGCCUGGGUCGUGGUGAGAUCAAGGUUUGGUUCUUAUGGGCAGGCCUCCUAAGCGAUGACUGAGUGCCACUGUGUGUUCCGCCAGGCAGCUGCUGCUGCUCUCCAUCCCUGCAUGGACAACGGACAUGGCAAACCAUCAACACUGCUCUCCUUGGAGGCUGUCUAGGGAGGUCCAGACAUCUUGGGAGAGACUGGGGUUCUCUUUUGCGCAAGAGAGCAUGGGCAGGCUCUGCGGGAGGCCCUUGGGGCAGGCAUCAGGGCUCUGGUCCUCCUUGCUUUGGCUCGGUGGGCCCGAGCUCUCCUGUCUCCCCAGGCCUCCUUUCCUCCGUGGGGUACAACUGGGCUCUGGGUGGGCAGGUGGGGGCUCCUGCAGGCAGUGCUGUUUUCUCCAAGGGGGAUGCACGUGACCCGCCAGACCCUCCUGGAAGCCGCCUCUUCUCAGGGUGGUUGUGCUCAGCCCCCACUUCCCGAAGGUCGGUGAGGCUGGGGCUACAGUUUCAGACCAGAGCAGGCAGUGCCACCGAGAGGGUGCCGCGCGAGGUAGGCCGGCGACGGGGCUUCCUGGGCCGCAGUGCCAUCCCGGCGACCUUGGCGAGGGGAUGGGAACGGGGUGUCCGCACAGCCAUUUCCAGGCGCCCGCGACGGCAGUAAGGGAGUGUCCCAGGCGUUGGUCCCGGCAGCCACACCUCGCUUCGCCUUUGCUCACUCAUGGAGAGCCCUCAGCCGCCUCCCACUGCCGCUCCUGAAUGCGCCUCACACAUCCAGAUUUGAAAGCACCCAUAGGGCCGCCGCCUCCCACCUCCCGAGGAAUCCGCUGCGCUGGGCCCGCAGGGAGGCAGGCUGGACGGCCCGGGCGCCUCCCCAUUGGUUGGCCGGGCCGGGCUCGACUCCCUCGCGCGGCUGCCGGCCACAGGCUCACCUCCCUUCCCGCCGCGCCCGGGGAGAGGAAGCGAGGUGGCCUUUACCCCUGCGCAGGCCGGCCAGGAAUGCGGGGCCGCGCUUCCCACUCUACCCGCCCGAGGGCUGAGGACGGCGGAGGCGAGAAGCGACGCGCAGAGUCCGGGCGCCGAGUGGUGGAGACGCGUCCCAGGCCGUUCGGAUCGGGGCUGCACACGGGCUGGGGCGAGGCCCGGGCCGCUGGUUCCCGCCCCCUCCCGGAGCCAUUCGUCCCCCGCAGACAACACGACGGGAGGGACCCACGCGCGGCCGCCGGUGCCCCUAGUCAGCCAAAAGCGAGCCCCACUGGCGGGCACCCCCACGAGGCCUGCGCCCGAGGUGCGCCGAUCUCCGGGUGCGCCGAGGCCCCCGAGGAGUCUGUAGAAGAGGCGACACCAGGGCUUCCAAAUGAACAACCGAAAGGAAGAUAUGGAAAUCACGUCCCACUACCGGCACCUGCUGCGGGAGCUCAACGAGCAGAGGCAGCACGGCGUCCUGUGCGACGUCUGCGUGGUCGUGGAGGGCAAGGUCUUCAAGGCGCACAAGAACGUCCUGCUGGGCAGCAGCCGCUACUUCAAGACGCUCUACUGCCAGGUGCAGAAGACGUCGGAGCAGGCCACGGUCACGCACCUGGACAUCGUCACGGCCCAGGGCUUCAAGGCCAUCAUCGACUUCAUGUACUCAGCGCACCUGGCGCUCACCAGCAGGAACGUCAUCGAGGUGAUGUCAGCCGCCAGCUUCCUGCAGAUGACGGACAUCGUGCAAGCCUGCCACGACUUCAUCAAGGCGGCGCUGGACAUCAGCAUCAAGUCGGACGCCUCAGAUGAGCUUGCGGAGUUCGAGAUCGGCGCCUCGUCCAGCAGCAGCACGGAAGCUCUCAUCUCGGCCGUGAUGGCUGGGAGGAGCAUCUCCCCGUGGCUGGCACGGCGAACGAGUCCUGCCAAUUCUUCCGGAGACUCGGCCAUCGCCAGCUGUCACGACGGAGGGAGCAGCUACGGGAAAGAGGAUCAGGAGCCCAAGGCCGAUGGCCCUGAUGAUGUUUCUUCACAGCCUCUAUGGCCUGGAGACGUGGGCUACGGGCCUCUGCGCAUCAAGGAAGAGCAGGUUUCACCGUCUCAGUACGGAGGGAGCGAGCUGCCUUCUGCCAAGGACGGUGCAGUACAGAACUCUUUCUCAGAGCAGAGUGCUGGUGAUGCCUGGCAGCCCACGGGCCGAAGGAAGAAUCGGAAAAACAAAGAGACCGUCCGGCACAUCACACAGCAGGUGGAAGAUGACAGCCGGGCCAGCUCCCCGGUGCCGUCCUUCCUGCCGACGUCGGGGUGGCCGUUCAGCAGCCGAGACUCAAAUGCGGACCUGUCCGUCACCGAAGCCAGCAGCUCCGACAGCCGAGGAGAGAGGGCCGAGCUCUAUGCACAGGUGGAGGAGGGUCUCCUGGGAGGAGAAGCCAGCUAUCUGGGCCCUCCCCUCACCCCAGAGAAGGACGACGCCCUGCAUCAGGCCACCGCGGUGGCCAACCUGCGCGCGGCGCUCAUGAGUAAGAACAGCCUGCUGUCGCUGAAGGCCGACGUGCUGGGGGAUGACGGCUCCCUGCUGUUCGAGUACCUGCCCAGAGGGGCCCACUCGCUGUCCCUGAAUGAGUUCACGGUGAUCAGGAAGAAGUUCAAGUGUCCGUACUGCAGCUUCUCGGCCAUGCACCAGUGCAUCCUCAAGCGACACAUGCGCUCGCACACGGGAGAGCGGCCCUACCCCUGCGAGAUCUGCGGGAAGAAGUUCACGCGGCGCGAGCACAUGAAGCGCCACACGCUGGUCCACAGCAAGGACAAGAAGUAUGUGUGCAAGGUGUGCAGCCGCGUCUUCAUGUCCGCCGCCAGCGUGGGCAUCAGGCAUGGCUCCAGGCGCCACGGUGUGUGCACCGACUGUGCUGGCCGCGGCAUGGCCGGGCCCCUGGACCAUGGCGGCGGAGGCGGCGAGGGCUCUCCAGAGGCGCUGUUCCCAGGCGACGGGCCCUAUCUGGAGGACCCUGAGGACCCACGAGGGGAGGCGGAGGAGCUGGGCGAGGACGACGAGGGCCUGGCCCCUGAGGAUGCGCUGUUGGCGGACGACAAGGAUGAGGAAGACUCGCCGCGGCCGCGCAGCCCCCCAGGAGGCCCUGACAAGGACUUCGCCUGGCUCUCCUAGGCCCGCCCGCCGGCAGGGUCGGUGGCUGCCUCGCUCCGUCCACCCGUGUGUGUGUCCGGUGGGUCUCCACUGCGGGGCCAGGGCCACGCUCACCCCUCUCGCGGCCCCUCCUCUGCUUCCCCCUGAACCCACCCCCCACGGAAACCAGCCCUGCGGGCUAAGCAGGUGCGACCCCAGCAAGAGGGGUGCUCUGGGACCAGACAUGAAGUGAGUUGGGGGAGGGCACAGGGUGGGUUUGAGUGAAGGGAGAGCACGGUCCUAAGUCCCCAGCAGGUGGUGCGGGUGUGUGAGUGGCCCCUGUGAUGGCCAGCCUGGCUUGGACACGUGAUGGGCCUGUGGCCGGGUCCAGUGGGCACUGGGCGGGGUGGUGUGUUCGGCCCAGAGGCCCCUGGCCUGAGCAGGUGCAGAGUUUUACAGACACCCGGUCAGCCCGGCUGGAGCCCGCCCUCCCCUCCCCUAGCAGCCAGGUCACUGCCUGUGGCUGCAGCCGUGGCCCGUGGUGCAGCCGUGGCCCAUGGCAGCCUGUAGAAUCCAGGUGCACAGAGAGCCCUGCCACCGUCUUACCUCUGGGCUUUGGUGCUUAACACACAACACAGCUGCAGACCCUGCUGGAGGCCGAGGGCUCCAGGUGCUAUCUUAGGUGGACACAGCCCUGGGGGCUCCUUCCAGGAGGGGACCCUCAGCCCUGUGCCCCCCACCACUUCAGGCCACACCAGGUUCCCUCUGCAAGGGCCUCGGCUCAGUCGUGUGCACUUCCUCGGAGAGCCUUGGGCUGCCACGUCCACCCCGGGCUCUGCCCGUCCUGUUCUGCCCAUGGCCCAGCCCGGCCGCUCCUGCUGACCCCUCCUGGACGGGCUGGAGCUGGGCUCCUGCCUUUGCUGCUAACACUGGAGGCGGUGUUCCUAACUGCAGUGUGCUGCUUACACCUCCCCGCGUGGGUAACCAAAUUUUUAAGUAGUCAGAGACAUAUCGAGGUAGUUACAUAAAAUUAUUUUGUUUGGCAUUAUUUUUCUCACUCGAAGAAACUAUAUAGGGUUGUUUUUCCUUUAGCUUGUGCUCAAGUCCUCUUGCUGUGUUUUCAGAAGCACUCACAUGUUCUUUCUUUUCCUGAGUGAAAAGCAAAGGUCCCACGGUGUGUGCUGUGGUGCACCGCCUGGCUUUGGGGGUCCCGGAGGCAGGCUGCCUAGACUCACAGCCUCGGGACCGUUGCCACGGCCUGUCUUCUCGUUCAGGCCUGCCUCUGACAGCACUCACCAUGAGGACAUUCCAUCCUUCACCCCCUCCUCUGGCACAGGCCACCACUGCGGUGCUGUGCCUUCAGAUGGGAGGUGGGCGCGGUGGCCUCCUCCUUCCCUCCAGGACCUGCCCGUGUGAAGACCCCCCGGAGUGCUGAGCUUCAGGGCUGCGUGGAAAGAGUUUUUACUCUCUUUUUCUAGCCUGUAUACCAGGCUUUUCCCCACAUUGUCAGGUAGAGCACCAGCUUCCCUGACCGCUGCUGCUCGGGGAGGGCUGGGGCUGGCCGGGGGUCCUGUGGAGGAGUACAUGGAGGACUCCAGGUACAGCGCAGGAGUCACGGCUUUUGUUUUUUGACAUUGGCCCCCGGUUCUACCAAUGACAGGGUGCCCUGGCUGGAGCUGUCAUCACACACACCCCUCAGCUCGGAGGCUGUGGGCUCCUCAAAGCUGGAGAAAGAGGCCAAGAUUUUUCUGCACACGGAGUGUGGGGAUAGGAGCCGGGCCAAGCGCUGGCCCCUCAGCGGUGAGCCCUGCCCACUCUUACCGAGCAAGGUGGGUGGCUCUGGCACGAGUCCCCCAGGGGGAGAGCAUGGCUACCAGGGAGCUGCAGCGGAGCCCUCCAGCCCUCACCCCAGGCCAGCCCCACCCCGGCCUCUUUGAGAAUUCUCAGAACUUUGUACCUUUCCCCUGAUUUUUAAACCCUUUUUCUAAACAGACUGACUUUCUUACAAAAUGCAUUUGGAAACCAGACCUUUGCUACCCACCAAUGUCUCUGGGUUUUGUACCAGUCCCUGCUCUCAGGCCACCCUGCCCAGGACCCAGGCCCGCCUCCCCCUCCACACUCAGGAUGUCCUGCUCCAUCUGGCCGGCUCACUCCGUGUGGCCUGCCUUUGCUGACCGUUUUGGGGUUCCCCGCCGGAGCUACAGGGGCAUUUUCUUCCCUAAAACCAACAGUGUCCCACUGACCUCCCCAAGUGUUUGCUGCGUGGCAGAUUUCCUGUUCUUGUUCGCAGUUUGCCGACUGAAGAGUGUGGGAUUUCCGAGGCCCAGGUGAGCACGUCCAUCUCAGGAGGCGUGGAGGGAAAAGACAUGUCAUGAAGGGUUUUUUUUAUGUGACUGAUUUUUUUUUAAAUCGAUGUUCAAACUAAUAAAUAUUUUUUUAUGAAGAGGAAAAAUGUGUAGAUUACAUUUCACAUUUUGUAUUUUUGUUUGUGUCUGUUUGUAUUUUGGUGUUUACAACACCAAAGUGGGAAAUACAGUCCAUUGGGGAUGGUGUUAUUUGGGGGCGGGGAGGGGGCAGGGACACCACGAUUUUUCUGUCAAGCUCUGGAUCCUGACCAGGUUGUACACUGGGGCUCUCUGAGCUUUGGGACACAGGACACUGCCAGGGCUACGUAGGGAACUGACUCAGAAGACGCAGCUUACUGCUUCCAACUUUGCACAUCUUCCUCUUUAAAAAACUGAGAAAAUGCAAAAACUGGAACUUUUUGCAAUAUUAUAAAAGAAGUAAUCUUAUUUUAGCUCAUUCUGUGACAUGUGCGACUCUUAAGAAAGCCAUACUUAAUGGUGGUGGUUUUUUUUAGAUCUUAUAUUGUGUUUUGUAUGCAGCCCUUUUAGAACUACUUGUAGUGAGGGUGCUGUGUGUGCUUUUCUUAAAUAUUUAUUUUUUUCAACAUGCUUUCAACCUGUCAACAAAAACAAAACACACAAAAAAAGGGCAGUGUUUGAAGAUUGUUGAUUUUUUUCUGGGGAUAAUCUAUAUUAUAUUGACUUCCUAUUACUUAUUAUAAACCUGUGUUUGUAUUGGAGAUGUGUCUACUAUUGGGGGAAGAGGUUCUCGUAAUCGCUCGGUGGGAAAUCAUGGCUCUGCCGUCCUGCCUCUCUGUGGCCGUGGGUUCACGUGGCCUCUGCGGUGAGUCUCCAAGUUUCUGCCUAGGCGCCUGUGCGUUUCCUUUCUGUGACGGGAUUAGCUUAGACAUCCUUGCAAAGCGAUCACUUUCAAUAAAUUGGGAAAUUGCUGCUCCA